GUGACACGAGGGAGCGCGAAGCGGAGGGCGCCUCGCGGCAGGAGCGGGAUUUCCGGGGUCACGGGAACCGGCAGGGGAACGGGAUAAAGUUCCCGGAGAAAGGAAAGGAGAGCGUGGGAUAGUAAAAGAGAAGACGCGGAGAAGAGGAGAGGACCUACAAGAACGGAGGACAGGGGCGCACGAUGGUCCCGGGGGGAGCGGAAACAAAGGCACGCAAAACGGAAAAGCGUGUGUAGGGGAGCGGAAAAGGAAGUCACCACCGUGGCCUGCGACGGACCCUUUCCAGCUUUUUGCCUGAAAGCUUUGCAGAAGAAAUGGCGAAAAGUCUUUUGAAGACAGCCUCUCUGUCUGGAAGGACAAAAUUGCUACAUCAAACAGGAUUGUCACUUUAUAGUACAUCCCAUGGAUUUUAUGAGGAAGAAGUGAAAAAAACACUUCAGCAGUUUCCUGGUGGAUCCAUUGACCUUCAGAAGGAAGACAAUGGCAUUGGCAUUCUUACUCUGAACAAUCCAAGUAGAAUGAAUGCCUUUUCAGGUGUUAUGAUGCUACAACUUCUGGAAAAAGUAAUUGAAUUGGAAAAUUGGACAGAGGGGAAAGGCCUCAUUGUCCGUGGGGCAAAAAAUACUUUCUCUUCAGGAUCUGAUCUGAAUGCUGUGAAAUCACUAGGAACUCCAGAGGAUGGAAUGGCCGUAUGCAUGUUCAUGCAAAACACCUUAACAAGAUUUAUGAGACUUCCUUUAAUAAGUGUUGCGCUGGUUCAAGGUUGGGCAUUGGGUGGAGGAGCAGAAUUUACUACAGCAUGUGAUUUCAGGUUAAUGACUCCAGAGAGUAAGAUCAGAUUCGUCCACAAAGAGAUGGGCAUAAUACCAAGCUGGGGUGGCACCACCCGGCUAGUUGAAAUAAUCGGAAGUAGACAAGCUCUCAAAGUGUUGAGUGGGGCCCUUAAACUGGAUUCAAAAAAUGCUCUAAACAUAGGAAUGGUUGAAGAGGUCUUGCAGUCUUCAGAUGAAACUAAAUCUCUAGAAGAGGCACAAGAAUGGCUAAAGCAAUUCAUCCAAGGGCCACCGGAAGUAAUUAGAGCUUUGAAAAAAUCUGUUUGUUCAGGCAGAGAGCUAUAUUUGGAGGAAGCAUUACAGAACGAAAGAGAUCUUUUAGGAACAGUUUGGGGUGGGCCUGCAAAUUUAGAGGCUAUUGCUAAGAAAGGAAAAUUUAAUAAAUAAUUGGUUUUUCGUGUGGAUGUACUCCAAGUAAAGCUCCAGUGACUAAUAUGUAUAAAUGUUAAAUGAUAUUAAAUAUGAACAUCAGAAUUACUUUGAAGGCUACUAUUAAUAUGCAGACUUACUUUUAAUCAUUUGAAUAUCUGAACUCAUUUACCUCAUUUCUUGCCAAUUACUCACUUGGGUAUUUACUGCGUAAUCUGGAACAUUUAGCUAAAAUAUACACUUUUGGCUUAAAAAUUAUUGCUGUCAAUUCCAAUAAUAAUUCUUAGCUUAUAACCAAAGAGCAGUGUUUAAAAGGAGAGCUUCUAUACAAAACCUAUUCCUGGCGUUACUUUUCAUACAAUUUUUGUUCUGUUUUACCUGGAAAUAAUUUACCAAAAUAACUGAGUGUUGCUGCUAAAGAACAAAAGUGGGGAGGUAUCAGGGAACAAGAAAACAAGAAAGGGUAUGAUCAAUCAUUUUCUUCUGCUCCAAACAGCUGGAGUAAAAUUCAUGGGAAAUGGCCCUUCAUUUAAAAAAAGAUGUACCUCACUACCCACUACAAAUUUGGAACUUUGUUCUUUUCAAUAAUUAGUUUUCUAUUGUAAAUUACCUACUAAACAGUGGUAGCCAUGACAUGGAAAGUCAACUGAUUCUACAAUUGGACAUUCAUUUGUGUGCCCUGGAAUUUCCAACUAGUAAUAAACAACUACUGUUGAUGUAGUUUUAAACCACUUGAAGGGACUCAUGAAGCAUCCUGCAACAUAAAUUUGCAUUUUUACAUCAGAUUUCUUUUUUUUCCUGAAAAACAACUAACCUUCUAACAACUAUCUUUCAAAAGUAAAUGUAAUAAAAAUGCACAACAUAAAAUGUUUAUGAUCCCAGCAAUACACUUUUUAAAAAAUGUGAAAGUCAAAGAAUUAAGUUCUAGUUCUGACUCAUCACAAGAGGUCAAAAGUAUUUGCUACUGUAACAUUCAAUUCACAUUUGAGAAUCAUGGUAAAAAUAACUUGCAUUUGCCUUACCAUCAUGAUCCUACUGUUGAGUUAGGAAAAUAUGGUUAGACAGACUCACAUUACUUUUUUUCAGAGGUAAACUCUAGAUUACUGUGUCAACCCAAUACUAUUUGGCCAUAGAUGUAAAAACUACCAAAUAAAAGUGGAUUUUGUGGUCUACAA